UGGGAUGCACCUUGAGCGGCGCCUUUCGUCGCAGCGCGCGGGCGGCCCGAGCUUCGGCGGCGGCGGCGGUAGCGGCGGCGGCGACGCUGACACCUCCCACCAUGGACAGCUUCGACUUAGCCCUGCUCCAGGAAUGGGACCUCGAGUCACUGUGAAGUCAAUGAAAGGAUUCUAUUUUGCAAAGCUGUAUUAUGAAGCUAAAGAAUAUGAUCUUGCUAAAAAAUACAUAUGUACUUACAUUAAUGUGCAAGAGAGGGAUCCCAAAGCUCACAGAUUUCUGGGUCUUCUUUAUGAAUUGGAAGAAAACACAGAGAAAGCCGUUGAAUGUUACAGGCGUUCAGUGGAAUUAAACCCAACACAAAAAGAUCUUGUGUUGAAGAUUGCAGAAUUGCUUUGUAAAAAUGAUGUUACUGAUGGAAGAGCAAAAUACUGGGUCGAAAGAGCAGCAAAACUUUUCCCAGGAAGUCCUGCAAUUUAUAAACUAAAGGAACAGCUUCUAGAUUGUGAAGGUGAAGAUGGAUGGAAUAAACUUUUUGACUUGAUUCAGUCAGAACUUUAUGUAAGACCUGAUGACGUCCAUGUGAACAUCCGGCUAGUGGAGUUGUAUCGCUCAACUAAAAGAUUGAAGGAUGCUGUGGCCCACUGCCAUGAGGCAGAGAGGAACAUAGCUUUGCGUUCAAGUUUAGAGUGGAAUUCGUGUGUUGUACAGACCCUUAAGGAAUAUCUGGAGUCUUUACAGUGUUUGGAGUCUGAUAAAAGUGACUGGCAAGCAACCAAUACAGACUUACUGCUGGCCUAUGCUAAUCUUAUGCUUCUUACGCUUUCCACUAGAGAUGUGCAGGAAAAUAGAGAAUUACUGGAAAGUUUUGAUAGUGCUCUUCAGUCUGCGAAAUCUUCUUUGGGUGGAAAUGAUGAACUGUCAGCUACUUUCUUAGAAAUGAAAGGACAUUUCUAUAUGUAUGCUGGUUCUCUGCUCUUGAAGAUGGGUCAGCAUGGUAAUAAUGUUCAAUGGCGAGCUCUUUCUGAGCUGGCUGCAUUGUGCUAUCUCAUAGCAUUUCAGGUUCCAAGACCAAAGAUUAAAUUAAGAGAAGGUAAAGCUGGACAAAAUCUGCUGGAAAUGAUGGCCUGUGACCGACUGAGCCAAUCAGGGCACAUGUUGCUAAGCUUAAGUCGUGGCAAGCAAGAUUUCUUAAAAGAGGUUGUUGAAACUUUUGCCAACAAAAUUGGGCAGUCUGCGUUAUAUGAUGCUCUGUUUUCUAGUCAGUCACCUAAGGAUACAUCUUUUCUUGGUAGCGAUGAUAUUGGAAAAAUUGAUGUACAAGAACCAGAGCUUGAAGAUUUGGCUAGAUACGAUGUUGGUGCUAUUCGAGCACAUAAUGGUAGUCUUCAGCAUCUUACUUGGCUUGGCUUACAGUGGAAUUCAUUGCCUGCUUUACCUGGAAUCCGAAAAUGGCUAAAACAGCUUUUCCAUCGUUUGCCCCAUGAAACCUCAAGGCUUGAAACAAAUGCGCCUGAAUCAAUAUGUAUUUUAGAUCUUGAAGUAUUUCUCCUUGGAGUAGUAUAUACCAGCCACUUACAAUUAAAGGAGAAAUGUAAUUCUCACCAUAGCUCCUAUCAGCCGUUAUGCCUGCCCUUUCCUGUGUGUAAACAGCUUUGUACAGAAAGACAAAAAUCUUGGUGGGAUGCGGUUUGUACUCUGAUUCACAGAAAAGCAGUACCUGGAAACUUGGCAAAAUUGAGACUUCUAGUUCAGCAUGAAAUAAACACUCUAAGAGCCCAGGAAAAACAUGGCCUUCAACCUGCUCUGCUUGUACAUUGGGCAAAAUACCUUCAGAAAACGGGCAGCGGUCUUAAUUCUUUUUAUGGUCAACUAGAAUACAUAGGGAGAAGUGUUCAUUAUUGGAAGAAAGUUUUGCCAUUGUUGAAGAUAAUAAAGAAGAACAGUAUUCCUGAACCUAUUGAUCCUCUGUUUAAACAUUUUCAUAGUGUAGACAUUCAGGCAUCAGAAAUUGUUGAAUAUGAAGAAGACGCACACAUAACUUUUGCUAUGUUGGAUGCAGUAAAUGGAAAUAUAGAAGAUGCUGUGACUGCUUUUGAAUCUAUAAAAAGUGUUGUUUCUUAUUGGAAUCUUGCACUGAUUUUUCACAGGAAGGCAGAAGACAUUGAAAAUGAUGCCCUUUCUCCUGAAGAACAAGAAGAAUGCAGAAAUUAUCUGACAAAGACCAGGGACUACCUAAUAAAGAUUAUAGAUGACGGUGAUUCAAAUCUUUCAGUGGUCAAGAAAUUGCCUGUGCCCCUGGAGUCUGUAAAACAGAUGCUUAAUUCAGUCAUGCAGGAACUCGAAGACUAUAGUGAAGGAGGUCCUCUCUAUAAAAAUGGUUCUUUGCGAAAUGCAGAUUCAGAAAUAAAACAUUCUACACCGUCUCCUACCAAAUAUUCACUAUCACCAAGUAAAAGUUACAAGUAUUCUCCCGAAACACCACCUCGAUGGACAGAAGAUCGGAAUUCUUUACUGAAUAUGAUUUGCCAACAAGUAGAGGCCAUUAAGAAAGAAAUGCAGGAGUUGAAACUAAAUAGCAGUAAGUCAGCAUCCCGUCAUCGUUGGCCCACAGAGAAUUAUGGACCAGACUCGGUGCCUGAUGGAUAUCAGGGGUCACAGACAUUUCAUGGGGCUCCACUAACAGUUGCAACUACUGGCCCUUCAGUAUAUUAUAGUCAGUCACCAGCAUAUAAUUCCCAGUAUCUUCUCAGACCAGCAGCUAAUGUUACUCCCACAAAGGGUUCUUCUAAUACAGAAUUUAAGUCAACCAAAGAAGGAUUUUCCAUCCCUGUGUCUGCUGAUGGAUUUAAAUUUGGCAUUUCGGAACCAGGAAAUCAAGAAAAGAAAAGGGAAAAGCCUCUUGAAAAUGAUACUGGCUUCCAGGCUCAGGAUAUUAGUGGCCGGAAGAAGGGCCGUGGUGUGAUUUUUGGCCAAACAAGUAGCACUUUUACAUUUGCAGAUGUUGCAAAAUCAACUUCAGGAGAAGGAUUUCAGUUUGGCAAAAAAGACCUCAAUUUCAAGGGAUUUUCAGGUGCUGGAGAAAAAUUAUUCUCAUCACGAUACGGUAAAAUGGCCAAUAAAGCAAACACUUCCGGUGACUUUGAGAAAGAUGAUGAUGCCUAUAAGACUGAGGACAGCGAUGACAUCCAUUUUGAACCAGUAGUUCAAAUGCCUGAAAAAGUAGAACUUGUAACAGGAGAAGAAGGUGAAAAAGUUCUGUAUUCACAGGGGGUAAAACUAUUUAGAUUUGAUGCUGAGGUAAGGCAGUGGAAAGAAAGGGGCUUGGGGAACUUAAAAAUUCUCAAAAACGAGGUCAAUGGCAAACUAAGAAUGCUGAUGCGAAGAGAACAAGUACUAAAAGUGUGUGCUAAUCAUUGGAUAACGACUACAAUGAACCUGAAGCCCCUCUCUGGAUCAGAUAGAGCAUGGAUGUGGUCAGCCAGUGAUUUCUCUGACGGUGAUGCCAAACUAGAGCGGUUGGCAGCAAAAUUUAAAACACCAGAGCUGGCUGAAGAAUUCAAGCAGAAAUUUGAGGAAUGCCAGCGGCUUCUGUUAGACAUACCACUUCAAACUCCCCAUAAACUUGUAGAUACUGGCAGAGCUGCCAAGUUAAUACAGAGAGCUGAAGAAAUGAAGAGUGGACUGAAAGAUUUCAAAACAUUUUUGACAAAUGAUCAAACAAAAGUCACUGAGGAAGAAAAUAAGGGUUCAGGUACAGGUGCGGCCGGUGCCUCAGACACAACAAUAAAACCCAAUGCUGAAAACACUGGGCCCACAUUAGAAUGGGAUAACUAUGACUUAAGGGAAGAUGCUUUGGAUGAUAGUGUCAGUAGUAGCUCAGUACAUGCUUCUCCAUUGGCAAGUAGCCCUGUGAGAAAAAAUCUUUUCCGCUUUGAUGAGUCAACAACAGGAUCUAACUUCAGUUUUAAAUCUGCUUUGAGUCUAUCUAAGUCUCCUGCCAAGUUGAAUCAGAGUGGGACUUCAGUUGGCACUGAUGAAGAAUCUGUUGUUACUCAAGAAGAAGAGAGAGAUGGACAGUACUUUGAACCUGUUGUUCCUUUACCUGAUCUAGUUGAAGUAUCCAGUGGUGAGGAAAAUGAACAAGUUGUUUUUAGUCACAGGGCAGAAAUCUACAGAUAUGAUAAAGAUGUUGGUCAAUGGAAAGAAAGGGGCAUUGGUGAUAUAAAGAUUUUACAGAAUUAUGAUAAUAAGCAAGUUCGUAUAGUGAUGAGAAGGGACCAAGUAUUAAAACUUUGUGCCAAUCACAGAAUAACUCCAGACAUGAGUUUGCAAAAUAUGAAAGGGACAGAAAGAGUAUGGGUGUGGACUGCAUGUGAUUUUGCAGAUGGAGAAAGAAAAGUAGAGCAUUUAGCUGUUCGUUUUAAACUACAGGAUGUUGCAGACUCGUUUAAGAAAAUUUUUGAUGAAGCAAAAACAGCCCAGGAAAAAGAUUCUUUGAUAACACCUCAUGUUUCUCGGUCAAGCACUCCCAGAGAGUCACCAUGUGGCAAAAUUGCUGUAGCUAUAUUAGAAGAAACCACAAGAGAGAGGACAGAUGUUAUUCAGGGUGAUGAUGUAGCAGAUGCAGCUUCAGAAGUUGAAGUGUCUAGCACAUCUGAAACAACAACAAAAGCAGUGGUUUCUCCUCCAAAGUUUGUAUUUGUUUCAGAGUCUGUUAAAAGAAUUUUUAGUAGUGAAAAAUCAAAACCAUUUGUAUUUGGCAACAGUUCUGCCACUGGGUCUUUGUUUGGAUUUAGUUUUAAUGCACCUUUGAAAAGUAACAAUAGUGAAACUAGUUCAGUAGCCCAGAGUGGAUCUGAAAGCAAAGUGGAACCUAAAAAAUGUGAACUGUCAAAGAACUCUGAUAUCGAACAGUCUUCAGAUAGCAAAGUCAAAAAUCUCUCUGCUUCCUUUCCAACGGAAGAAUCUUCAAUCAACUACACAUUUAAAACACCAGAAAAGGAGCCUCCAUUAUGGCAUGCUGAAUUUACCAAAGAAGAAUUGGUUCAGAAGCUCCGUUCCACCACAAAAAGUGCAGAUCACUUAAACGGCCUGCUUCGGGAAAUAGAGGCAACCAAUGCAGUCCUUAUGGAGCAAAUUAAGCUUCUCAAAAGUGAAAUAAGAAGAUUGGAAAGGAAUCAAGAGCGAGAGAAGUCUGCAGCUAACCUGGAAUACUUGAAGAACGUCUUGCUGCAGUUCAUUUUCUUGAAGCCAGGUAGUGAAAGAGAGAGACUUCUUCCUGUUAUAAAUACGAUGUUGCAGCUCAGCCCUGAAGAAAAGGGAAAACUUGCUGCGGUUGCUCAAGGUGGGUAAAAGGAGAGUCUCAGAACUUCUGACUUCUAACUUAAACUAAACAGCCUGGUGGUUGAGAAGUUGUCUGUAUGUGUAACUUUUCAAUUUUGCUCAUUUGAAUUGGGUCUGUCAUAUGAGUAGGCCGUGACUAGAUUUGAAAAGCUGACUUUUUAACAUCUUGAGGCAACUGUAGUACAUUUAUAUAAUUUUAACGUUCAGCAAAAUACAAUAAGUGCUUAGCUUGAUCUUCUAGCUCUUUGAAAAUUGGAUUUUUAUCCUGGGGUUGAGUUCUGGUGUUCAGCUGAACGUGGUUUUGUUUUAAAUUCUACUUUUUAAAAAACAUUUAUUAGCUUGUUCCUUUUCUACUUCACGCCUCUUCCUUCCUCCAACCCCAAAUAGCCUAAGACAAUGGAGCCAUAGAGCCCAACACUUGGUCUAUAUACAGCAGUCCACUUUCUAGGCAAAUGCAGUUUUAAAACUGUGCCAUAGGCCAGGCGCCGGUGGUUCACGCCUAUAAUCCCACCACUUUGGGAGGCCGAGGCAGGCGGAUCACAAGAUCAAGAUACCGAGACCAUCCUGGCCAACAUGGUGAAAUCUCGUCUCUACUAAAAAUACAAAAAUUAGCUGGACGUGGUGGCAUGCGCCUGUAGUCCCAGCUACUCAGGAGGCUGAGGCAGCAGAGUCGCUUGAACUCACGAGGCGGAGGUUGCAGUGAUGUGUCACGCCACUGUACUCCAGCCUGAUGGCAGAGCGAGACUCCAUCUCAAAAAAAAAAAACAAAAAACUAUGAUGUAGUUAGAGUUGGUUUCCAUGUCAGAUGGAUUUAAUACUGUGAUGUCAUUAACUUCUUUGAAAUGCUUCAUAUACAACUGCUAUAGUUAACUGAAUUCAAGCUGCAUCUUAAGAAUUAUGGUUUCGUUUUUGUUUUAGUUUUAAAUUACUUUUAUUUUUGACAUUUACAAGCACAAGGAAGACGCUAUAAUCUCUCUUGAGUUGUCACCCAUCUCUAACAGUUUUCAACUCAUGGACAAUCUUUUGGCGUAACUAGGGGAGAGUUAGAGACUUAAAUCCCACACAUCAUUUCUUUCCCCAGUGAAUAAUUCAAUGUUUAUUGGAUUUCUCUGUCACCUAUACCUAGUUUAUGUUCAUUUUGCCUGUGUUAUUGUGAAUGUCUUUUUAUAGUAUCCUAAAUAGGGCUCAUAUAUUGCAUUUGGUUGAUAUUCCUUAAGCUUUAUUUUGUUGUUGUGUUUUUGUUUGUUUGAGACGUAGUGUUGCUCUGUCACCCUGGCUGGAGUGCAGUGGUCCGAUCAUGGCUCACUGCAACCUCCGCCUCCCGGAUUCAAGUGAUUCUCCUGCCUCAGCCUCCCAAGUAGCUGGGACUACAGACGCACGCCAGCUAAUUUUUCUAUUUUUAGUAGAGACGAGGUUUCACCAUGUUGGCCAGGAUGGUCUCAAUCUCCUGACCUUGUGAUCUGCCCGCCUUGGCCUCCCAAAGUGCUGGGAUUACAGGUGUGAGCCACCACACCCAGCCAUUUUGUUGUUUUUUUAUCUAUAACAAUUAUAUAUAUAAGUAUAUUUUUAAUGUGCCACUUAUUAAUUGAAGAAAGUGGUCAUUUAUGCUAUAGCAGUUCUAUAUUUGGGUUUUAAUCAUUACAGGGUAACACUGAGCUUGUUCCAAUUGCCUAUAAAUAGGAAGAUCCAGGUGCAAUUGGGUGGGAUGGUGGACAAAAAUACAUCAUAGAUGGUAUUGUGUGCUUUCUAAGACAUGAGGAGGCCCAGAAUGUCCAGACAACUUACUUUUGACUGAUUGACCUUAUCUAGUUGGUGUUCUUUAACAUGUUCCCCAUCCCCUGUAAACCCUAAUAACUAAACUGAUAAGAGUCAUCCUCAAAAUUGAGCAGGCAUCUGAAUCAUCUGGUAUACUUACUAAAAUUCCAAUUGCUGGUCCCCAAUUUCUGACCCAAGAUUCUGCAUUUUUAGCAAUUUGUUGCUGAUGCUUCUGGUCUGGGGCCCAUACCUUGAGAACCCCCGGUCUAGAGGCCUGAUAAGAUUCAGGCUUAAUUUUUUUUACAGACAUACUUCAUAAGUAGUAUUGAUAGUUUCUUUGAAUCUGGUUUUUAAUAAUCUUUCUAAUGAUGAAGGAGGAAUGUUCUCAAUACUGACAGUAAUCUCAGUUCUUCAAACUAUAGGAUAGGUUUCUAUAGCCACAAUAGUAUUUUUGUCACAAGGGCCCAAAUAAGAAUACAUCAUGUAUAUUUUUAAUACUUAUUCAAAUUACAAAUUCACUGUCUUUAAUUUAUUCUAACAAAAGUAAACCUAAUUUUAUAGUUAUAAAAAAGAAGAAAUCUACUUCUAGUCACCUAAGAGUAAAACUGCCCUUAUAAAAAACAAGACAGAAAUCUCAAAAUUAUAACUAAUUUUAUAGUUAUAAAAUUAACCAGGACUUUAAGAACGUUUGCAUUUUAAAAUUAAAGUUUUCAAUAGUUUUCAAUACAACAAUGAUACUAUCUCAAAAUACUCAGCAUGUCUAACAGGCCUCUUUUAAAAGCUCAGCAUGUUUAAUGUAGGUGUUGCUAACGUCCAGGUGGCUCCUAUAAGUUAAGGGUCCAUUGAUUUAGAAGUUCUAAAAGAGACUAACCUAAGGGAUACCAAUAACAGAUAUUUUUAAAGAAUUUCAUAGAGGAGAUACACAUUAGAAACCCAGAACUCUAAGAUGUGCAUUUGCUAAGUCCUGUAAACAGACAGGAAAACACAUUUACAUUAGUUUGCCCUUUAAAGAUUAUUUCCUACUUGUCUCUUAUCAAUGUGAGUACAUAAAAGAGACCUUAUUACAAUUAAAAACAAUGAUGGUUUAGCAGCAGAUUUAGAUACCUUACAUUCUCUCUUUAAGAGAGAGAAUGUAAGGCCUGGUGCGGUGGCUCACACCUGUAAUCCAGCACUUUGGCAGGCCGAGGAGGGUAGAUCACCUGAGGUCAGGAGUUCGAGACCAGCCUGGCCAACAUGGUGAAACCCCGUCUCUACUCAGAAUACAAAAAUUAGCCGGGCGUGGUGGCGCAUGCCUGUAAUCCCAGCAACUUGGGAGGCUGAGGUAGGAGAACUGCUUGAACCCAGGAGGCAGAGGUUGCAGUGAGCCGAGAUGGUGCCAUUGCACUCCAGCCCAAGCAACAAGAGCAAAACUCCUAUCUCAAAAAAAAAAAAAAAAAAAAAAAAAAAUAAAAAAAAAAAAAAAGAAUGUAAACUACAAGAUGGUUCAAAAGAAAUUACACGGAAUUCAGCAUGGGAGAAACAAAAAACAAGAGUGGGAAAAGACAUCAAACAUGUUUUUACUAAUCGAAGUUCUAAAAGGAGAGACGAGAAUACAGCACAGAUAAUAUAUGAAGAGAAUGGCUGGAAAUCUUUCAGAACUGUUGAAGGAUAUCUAUCCACAGAUUCAAAAACCCAAUAAAAUCUCAAGCAGUAUUAAAAAAAAAAAGAAGAAAUCUACUUCUAGUCACAUAAGAGUAAAACUGCCCCUAAAAAAGACAGAGAGAAAUCUCAAAAGCAGCCAGAGAAAGAAGACACAUUGCCUCACAAUAGACUUCUCAACAGCAUUGGUGUAAUACUAUCUCAUGUACUAAAAGAAAUAACUGCCAACCUUUUAUAUUUUCCAAGAUCUCUUCUGGAAAACAAAAACUUUAAGAAUCUGCCUUCACUGGAAAUUCUUAAUGAUGUACUUCAAGCAAAAAGAAAAUUUCCUAGGUAAAAGGUCUAAGAUGCUAGAAAGAAAGACAUGCAAAGGAAACUUACCACCAUAUUACAGAUAUGGACUGUCAGUCUGACUGGUCACACUAGGGGCAUUUUGUUACCAAGGCCUUGAAAAUAAUAACCAACACUGCAUACAUGAGGGAUGCCAGAAGAAAGGUCUGAGAGCCACUCUUCCUGGCACUGAAGGAAACAGGGCCCAUCAGAGCAAACAAGUACCUUUUGCCUCUCUCAUCUCCUUGGAGGCAAAUGUUUAUAAUCUCUGGUUUUGUGUAAAGUUUAUAACAGUAUUUUUCAUUCAGGUUGCUACCUAUUAGUGGAUGGUGAAAUUAAUUUGGUGGAUCACAUUCAGGAUAUUUUUUUUUUAAAUCAAAAGAAUACAAGCUGGGCUCAAUGACUCACACCUGUAAGCCCAACAGUUUGGGAAGACCAGGCAGGAGGAUUGCUUGAGAACAGGAGUUCAGAAUCAGCCUGGGCAACAUGGCGAGACCCUAUGUCUACAAAAAUUUUAAAAUAUGCCAGAUCUGGUGGCAUGUGCCCAUAGUCCUAGCUACUCGGGAGGCUAAGGCAGCAGGAUUGUUUGUUAGAAGGAGUUCGAGGCUGCAGUCAAACUUCUGGUCGAAAUCCUGGUCACGCCACUGCAUUUCAGCCUGGGCAACAGAGUAAAACCCCAUCUUUAAAAAAAUAUUAAGAAAUAAAAAUAAUAUGUGAAACGUUAGAAUAUGUUGAAUCUGGUAAGGAUAAGCAAUUAUUUCUUGAAACUCUACAUACAUACAUGAGUGUUGGUAAAUACCUGACUGUAUCAUCAGCUCUAGAUAUAAAAUGUUUAUGAUGUUGGCUGUGAGUUAAUGAGGAAUAGUUUUCCUUUCUGUGGGUUUGGGUGUAUUUGGGAAACAUUAGCUUAGGAGGGUAAAGUAGGUUACCCAACUCUGAAAAGCAGCAUCAAAAUCUUUAUAAUAAACACAUAUUAGGGGCCCAACUUAAAUUUCAAGCAGAUGUCAUGAGCUGCUCAGAGUAGCAUGUUACAACUCUGCGUUAUAAGGUAAAAUGACUUAGAGUGUAGCAGUAGUCCCCAAUGUCAAAUAGACAGUGGUAAGUAUAGAUUGCUCUUCUCCUUGCAUCACAAAUGUUAAUUCACCCUGCCCCCACACGCAUUAAAACUCAGCAUAUUUCACAAAUUGAGUGUUUCAUUUCUAUUUGAGAUAGACUUAUGGUAAGUCAGCUUUGCUCCCCAAAUAAGUUAGCCAUAUAGUACUUCUAUAUGCAAAAUUUGAAUCUCAAUUUUACUACUCAAGCUGGAAGUAAAAGUCAUUUUUGUAUAUCUUCUUUGCUCCCAGACUGGGUUACAGUUUACAGAUCUGAAUAUUGUCACUUGUACACCAUACAUACACAGAGGUCUAAAACUCUCUACAAGUAAAUAAAGAAAAAAAGCCCAGCAACCCAAUAGGAAAAUAGGCCAAGCCUGUUAUAGGCUUUUUGAUCAUCUCCAGACUGGCAGGAAGAGAAUGCAUACUCACACUGUAAGUGCCUGAUUUGAUUUGCAGAGGAUAUAGAACCUUAUCAGAAAACAGCCUUCCAAGGCAAGAGCAAAUGCACCCUAUCUAAGCACAGCUUUUCUCCAAUUCUUAUUUACCUAAGGAGAUGAAUAGCUGCCAGGAACAUUGUUUGCACAAGGGCAGGAGCCUGCCAGAUCUGAGAACACAGCAAAAUUUUUAUUUUGUCAAAAAUCUUAUAUUCAGCUUACACCAUUCAUUUCAGGUGAACAUACAACAGUCUGCAUUUCAGUUUAGGGAAAUGUUUACAGUCGUCUGGUUCUCUUUAUUCUUGGGAACAAGGUUACCUCACUUGGAACACAUAACCAGUGCCAAGUUGUCCAUCCCUAAGCAAUAUCGCUUCCUCCUACUUUCUAGAAGUUCUUCAGGUUGUGGAAGACAGACUUUUCAGAAUUGUUUGCCCUCAUUCCCUCCUCCAGAAAUGCAUGCCUUUGUAUAAUCUCUUCCCCUUGAGAGCCAGUAGGCUAACCUAAUGAGUUAUGUUUAACCAGUAGAAUACAGCAAGAAUGAUAGAUUACAAGAGAUUGUGGCUUCUAUCUUGCUAGCGGCCUCUCUCUGUCUUCUCUGCUUGCACACUUUGUUGAAGCAAGCUACCAUCCCAGAGGCAAGGAACACAGGCCAUCAGUUUAGCAGCCUUGAGGAACUAAAUUCUUCCAACUACCACAUAAGUUUGGAAGUAGAUUCUUCUCCAGUCCAGCCUUCAGAUGAGACCCCAGCCAUGCCAACAUCUUGAUUGCAGCCCUGUGAGAGACCUUGAAAUAGAACCAUUUCUGAUCUCCUGACCCACAGAAACUGUGAAAUAAAUAUGUGUUAAGGUACUAAGUUUGUAGUAAUUUGUUACGCAGCAGAUUGUAAAUAACACGCAGAUAAAACCAGACAGAACAGAAAAAUAAAAUGACUUUAACUCUAGAAAGUUUCCCCAUGUAAAAUUUUGAAAAUGCUACUCUGCCUAAGGUCAAACUGUCAUACAUAUAUACGUAUGAAAACACAGAAAGGUGUCUGGAAGGGUAAUACCAAAUUAAAUCUUUAUCCAAGAGGAAUGAAAACCAGUAUUCACACAAAAACCUAUGCACAAACCUUGUGAAUAUAUUAAAAACCAGUGAAUUAUGCACUUUAAAAAGGUGAAUUAUGUGGUAUAUGAAUUAUAUCUCCAAAACAUUUAAUUAAAAACCUGUACACAAUUAUUCGUAGAAACUUUCUUUAAAAUUGCUAAAAACGAGGAAGAUCUCAGUUAUCCUUCAACUGGCAAAUGAAUAAACAAACUGGUACAGCCGUGCAAUUGAAUACUGCUCAGCAAUAAAAAAGAAUGCACUGCCAGUUCAGCAACAUGGGUAAUUCUCAAAUGCAUUAUGCCAGUUGACAGAGGUCAGACUCAAAAUACUAUGUACAGUGUGAUUCUACUUAUAUGACACUGAAAAAAGCAGAACUAUAAGGACAGAAAACAGGUUAGCGGUUGCCAAGGAGUGGGAGAAGCAGCCAGGGAGAACUUUGAGGAGAUGAAAAUGUGCCAGGCCUUGGUCGGUGGUGGUACGUAACUGUGCAUUUGUCAAGACUCAGUGCUAUAUGCUGAAAAGGGCAGGUUUUACUAUAAGUAAGUUGUACCUCAAUAAACAUGAUUUUUAAAUGAUUAAAACUUUGGUUUUUGUUUGUUGUGGUUCAGUUUUAAGGUUUCCCAUAAAUCUAUUGGUUUUAGAUUCUAAGUUGUAUAUAAGCUUCUGUUUUAAAAGAAUUUUUUUUUAAAUCCCCUUAUCGUCAACAAUAUUUAGUUGUGCUGGAAAUUUUAUUUUGGAAUUGUUUAAUAGAGAAAGACAAUAAAUAAUGUUCAAGAACAGACAUUGAUUCAUAACAUCAAAGUAUAUUGUGAGAAGAUGGUAUUUCAGAAUAGAGGAAGAAUUUCUUAUGUGCUGGUAAGAUUGUAGAUAAUCAUUUCUGCAUAAUUUUCAUAGCUGGAUUGCUUUAAUAAAGCCAUUUAAAGGUUAAGUUCUAGAUUGCUUCAUGUUGCUUAUCAAUGUUUUAAAGCUAAAAUAGAAAAUUAGCUGUUAAGUUGGCUCAACCGGAAAUUCAGUAUAUCCUUUAAAAAGAGAAAUUUAGUAAGCAGUGUGUCUAAAGAAUGACAUAUGGUUGGGUACAGUGGCUCGUGACUGCAAUCCCAACACUGUGAGGCUGAAGUGGGAGGAUCACUUGAGCCCAGGAAUUUGAGACCAGCCUGGAAAACAGUGAGACCUGCAUCUCUACAAAAAAACAAAAAAUUACCCAGGCAUGGUGGUACACACCUUGUGGUCCCAGUUGCUUGGGAGGCUGAGGUGGGAGAAUCACUUGAGCCUGGGAGAUCAAGGCUGCAUUGAAGUCUCAUCACGCCACUGCACUCGAGCCUGGGUGACAGAGCAAGACCCUAUC